GUCACGUGGGGCUGCGCCCAAGGCUGCCGGGAGCAGACUGGGCUGCGGGCGGCGGGGCCGGCGCCUGCCUGGAGGGAUGGGGCUGCCGGGCGCGUAGGGGCCAUGCCGCCCGGGACCCGGGCCUGCCGCGUUCCGCGCCCCGGCCGCCGCGCCCCACGUCCGCGCCGGGAUGGUGAACCUGGCGGCCAUGGUGUGGCGCCGGCUUCUGCGGAAGAGGUGGGUGCUCGCCCUGGUCUUCGGGCUGUCGCUCGUCUACUUCCUCAGCAGCACCUUCAAGCAGGAGGAGAGGGCAGUGAGAGAUAGGAAUCUCCUCCAGGUUCAUGACCAUAAUCAGCCCAUCCCGUGGAAAGUGCAGUUUAACUUGGGCAAUAGCAGUCGUCCGAGCAAUCAGUGCCGCAACUCCAUUCAAGGGAAGCACCUCAUCACGGAUGAACUCGGCUACGUUUGCGAGAGGAAGGAUUUGCUGGUAAAUGGCUGCUGUAAUGUCAACGUCCCUAGCACGAAGCAGUACUGCUGUGAUGGCUGCUGGCCCAACGGCUGCUGCAGCGCCUAUGAGUACUGUGUCUCCUGCUGCCUGCAGCCCAACAAGCAACUUCUCCUGGAGCGCUUCCUCAACCGGGCAGCCGUGGCAUUCCAGAACCUCUUCAUGGCAGUCGAAGAUCACUUUGAGUUGUGCCUGGCCAAAUGCAGGACCUCAUCUCAGAGCGUGCAGCAUGAGAACACCUACCGGGACCCCAUAGCAAAGUAUUGCUAUGGAGAAAGCCCGCCCGAGCUCUUCCCCGCUUGACGGGUGCAGCGGACUUGCUCCAGCCUGGGUGAGGAGGCCCCGCUGAAGAACUCGCCUCCUGGGACCCAGCUUCAGCCAUCGGGCCAGGCUGCAGGAAGAAGACAAAGGCAGCGUGAGGAAACCUUGGCUUUGACCCCUUCUCGUGUUGUCAUCUUUGGCUUCGCUCACCACCCGGGCUUACCAGAUGGAACUCUUCUGUAAAGCAGCUUGGCCCCUCCAGCCAGUCCCAUUCGGGAAAGAUGAAACCGGAGGCCGGGCUCACGGUGGUGGUGGAGUUCUUGGAUGACUCAGCCCUGGGACCUGCACAGGGACCUGUGACUUGUGUUCAUCGGGGGCCGGUGUCACUUCCAGUUUUGAUCCAGGCUCUUUCACUGUAAAAUUAUUUAUUGGAUUCCUUUGGAGUAAUGGGAACAUUCUAAUGUUUUAUGUAGGAAAAUGCCUUGCCAUUCUAGUUGAAUAUGUUCAAGGAAAUUAUUUUUGUUGUUGUUCUGUGUUCUCGAGUUUCAGGAGUUAAAUCAUUCUUCCACCCAGAUACAACAUUUUCUCUUUUAGGACGUGAAUAUUCUCUCUAGGCAGUUAUUUUUGUUUGUAUUUCGACAGUAUCAAGCAUAGGCCCUGAACGUGACCUGUUAGCCAUAUCCUGACGUGUAAAAUUAUCUAAAAACUCAGACACUCUUCCAUUCUAAUCUAACUGCACGAUUUCUAACAGUGGGCACCAUGUGCCUGCCCUCAGGUUAUUUUCCAGUGGUAGUCGAAUGUGCUCAUAUACCCUAUGGAGAGCACUGUUUUAGCAGAAAUCUAAUUUCUCUUCCUGGAGGAAUUUGUUCUCAUUUCUUUUGCCACUUAAAAUUAACUGUGGGCUACUCAGCCAGGGUACAGUGGGAGCCUCAGGAAGGUCAGAGGCAACCUCCUCCCCUGUUCUAUCAAUAGAAACCCAACGUUGAGGCAAUUCCUAAACAGACGCACCUCGUAGCUUGCUGUAUGUGUUUAUUCUUUAUUGCUUUCAGCUUUGGGGCUGUAACAGGUACAAAUAUUUGGUUUCCCUAUGAUUUAUAGAGAAGAAGAAGAAACCCAGCUUUCUAUCAGAGCACUGCAAGAGAAGAGUCUUACACCUGCCCUCAGUGGGAGAUGAGAAUGGUCAUUAUGACUUAGAGAAUGCUACACGUGUAGGUUGCUGGUGUGUCCUGAAUCCACAGGCAUAAAGCACUCCCCAUUUUUCCUACUGUAAUGCAGAUUCUCCGGCUCAAGGUCUAGAAUAUUUGAUCCUAAGAUCAAGACAUCAUGCCCUUCGAAUAGUACUGCUCUUUGUUUUCAGGAGUCACGUGAACACACAACUCUCCUAUAUUCCUCACGAACCUCAGGAUUGAGCAAGGUCUUUGUAAUUUUUUUGGUUCACUUUAUUGACCUGGGAGCAAGGUGCUAAUUCUGUGGUCAGUAUUCAAUGUUUUUUUCAGUGGAGCUUUUUCUUUGGGCCAUAUUUGCCUUCUAAUACAUUCCUGCAAUAUGUAGUGGUGAUUUCCCUUAGCUUCCUCCUACUACCUCUUAUACUCAUCUCCCCAAAUUAUUUGCCUCCCUUAAAUAAGUUUUCCUAGAAGGUAAGCUGGUCAGGCAAUUUGAAAAAUAUUAGAUCCCAAGAAAUCUAUUCCGUUUGCAUUGGACUUCUCGGAUUCCAUGUGUUUGCAGCAGGACUACAUCGAACUCUGAUGUGCCGGAUUGUGGCAUGUCUGCAUGUCUCAUCCAUCUAUUGUUUUUGGUAACUCAGUUUGGAAUUUCAGUGUCUGUCUUCCCUGGGUUGACAUUGGAAUCAGCCUCUCCUUUGAGCUUAUUUUAACUCUUGAGCAACAUAACAUAGAUUUAAUGUGAACAGUUUAUACCAAAGGGCAGCCUGUGCCUGUUUAUGGAUCCUCUCUGCCUUUGUACUUGAAGAGCGCAUUUUACAUUUCCAGUCCUUUCACAGACAGGAGCUCCAACCUUACGAUGGAGAAUUAAACUUGCUUGUAUUUCCACUUUGUGGAUGAGGAACUAUGAGAGGUGGAGUGACUUCCUGGGUCCCCGCUGAGACUUAGUGACAGAUCCCAGACAAGAACUUCAUCUCUGACUCCAGGUCUAGUCCUCUUCCCCCUGUCUCUUGCCAACUCCAGCCCUGACACCGUGGGCGUCUCCCCUGAGAGCAGAUAUAUUUCAAUUGUCCAGGCCAAAAGAGGGGCGAGGCGGCAUAAACACCCAAAUUAGGUGGAGGAUCCAAAAGUCAUUUUCAUUUGGCUGUGGAAUAUGUUUUUUGUAUUUCAAUCAGCUAGGGGUGUGUUCACUGUUUUUGGAAAUUCACAGCGCUUGAGCCUCCAUAAUGAAGCUGGGCUGCAGAGCACCUGGCACGUGCUCCAGGCUCCCAGCUCCCAACCUAGGACCUCUCCCUGCCCUCCACUCUGGUUGGUUUGUGGUUCCCUCGACCGAGGGUUUCUAGAAUCAGGGACCUUGUCUAAGUUUUGUUUGCCCAGAGCCCAGCGAAGUGUGUGAUACACCUUGGGAGUUUAGGAGAUCACAAAAGGGAUGAAAACACCUUUAGAAAACAUUUCAUUGGUGGGGCGUGGUGGCUUAUGCCUGUAAUCCCAGCACUUUGGAAGGCUGAGGCAGGUGGAUCACCUGAAGGCAGGAGUUCAGACCAGCCUGACCAAUAUGGUGAAACCCCAUCUAUACUAAAAAUACAAAAAUUAGCCGGGUGUGGGGGCGUGUGCCUGUUUUUGUGAGACUCUGUCUCAAAAAAAAGAAAAAAAUAUUGUUAAUAAGUGAGUGUUUUCGGCUCAAGGGAAUUGAGUCAUACGUUGCAUCUCCCCCAGUUCUGCAUCUUAUUUGCUGCGCUUGCUGGAGUUGUAAAGAUUGGUCCUAACAGGGAAAGAAGCACACAAGAGACUGUGAAAAGGGCUCUGAGACAAGCAAGGACAAAAGAGGGAGGGAAAUACCUUCCACAGGGCCUGGGAUCUGGCAAUGCUAGAGCCUUUUUUUUUUUUUUUUUUUUUUGCGAUGGAGUCUUGCUCUGUUGCUCAGGCUGGAGUGCAAUGGCGUGAUCUCAGCUCACUGCAACCUCCCCCUCCUGGGUUCAAGCAAUUCUCCUGCCUCAGCCUCCUGAGUAGCUGGGAUCACAGGCGUACACCACCACACCCAGCUAAGUUUUUGUACUUUUAGUAGAGACGGGGUUUCACCAUGUUGGCCAGGCUGGUCACGGACUCCUGACCUCAGAUGAUCUGCCCGCCUGAGCCUCCGAAAGUGCUGGGAUUACAGGCGUGAGCCACUGCGCCCGGCAUGGAGCUGCUAUUGAUGGGUGAGCUCCACAGCUUUUGCAGAAGCAGAGGAUAUGACUUGAGAGCAGUGCUGUCACCUCUCAGCAUGUCCCCAAGCCCAACUGGGGCCUCCUGGAGAUGCCUCAGUCGGCACUGGCCCCAAGGGAAUCGUGGGGAACAGUUGCACAAUUUGCAAGUUUCUGAGUGCAGCUUUUCCCAUCCUUGGGAUCAGCAGAUAAGUUGUAAACACAGGGAGGUACUGCUUAUUGGAUAUACUUUUCAUAAGUAGGACAGAAUUCUUUUGGGACUCUAGAGUUGGGAACUACCACUUACUAGCGGCGUGGCUGAGGCAGUCUUCCUCCUCUGUGGCUCAGGCCCUUCAUCUGUGAAAUGGGGUCACAGCAUCUGCCUCUCAGGGUCACUGUGAGGUGUCGAUGUGAGCAAGGCCUGAGGCUUGGCAAGAAGUCAAUGUCUGCAACUCAGCAGGGAGCAAUGGCAGGGGCAGUCAGGGGUCGGCUCGGAUAGGGGUGGGUGGGCUCCUGAGGUUGGAAGGGUAGGAAUUACAGAGCUCUUGUUACUAUUGUUGUUACUGUUUUUAAAGAUACGAUAUUUCAGAUAAUUCAGGAGCACGUAAGGAUGAAACUUAGGAUAACCUAAAAUCACACAACCUAGAGAGAAGCGCAUUUUUGUCUUCCCCCAUUUUCUAGGCAAAAAUGAAAGUACUUUGUCCUCUUGAAAAACAAUUCUCUAAUGAAUAUCCUAUGUUACAUAGAGGCCUGUGUAAUGCAUUUGUGUGGCCACAUGGUGUCAAUUUCAUGAAUAUACAAUAAUAUUAUUAAUUCCCUGCUGAGGACAUUAACUGGUUUCCAAGGCUGCUUGUUGUUUUUGCUACUACAAAUAAUGCAUUGAUGAUAAAUACUUUUACAUACAUGGUUGUAUGUUUAUCUGAACUAUUUUCACCAAUAUAUUCACCUAGUGUGUAUGGAAGUGUCCAUUUUUGUCAUACCCCUGGUAACCCUGUGAUAUUAUUUUUAAACAUUUUGCUAAUGGAUCUCUGUUCUUGUUUGAAUGUAUUUAAUUUCCAGCAGAAUGAGCCCCAUUCCUUAUUUUGAUUGGCCAUUUAUCAUGUACAUAUGGUGAAAUGCCUAUUCGUGACUUAGCCAAUGUUGUUUCUUUUUCUUACUGAUUACUACAGUACAUUUUUAUAUGAAAGCAGCCUUUGUCCCCUUCUCUUGUUUUUCAGCCCUGUGUUAGAAACAACUAAGCUCACAUAUUCACAAACCAACUUUUCCAGUUCAUCUAGGGCAGUGGUGCUCAACAGGGGCAAUUUUGCCCCCCAGGGAACAUUUGGCAAUGUCUGGAGACAUUUUUGUCACAGGUGGGGAGGAGGGCAGUACUGUGGGCACUCGUGGAGGGAGGCCAGGGAUGGUGCCCAACAGCCCCCACGACACAGAAUUACCUGGCUGGAAGUGGGAGCCGGGUGGAGGGAGGGAAGCCCUGCUCUGGGGUCAUAUCUCCCCGUUAGAUUGAACAGAGGAGCUCCUGGUAGCUGAGUGCUGACUUCAUUAUUUUUCCCCGCCCUUGCUUUCUACCCUGCUGAAGUGCUGCUGAUUAAAUUACCCUGAAAUCCCCACAGGACACAUUACUUCCUCACAGGUCUCUACUAGCCCAGCGCUGCCUCAAGGAAUGGCAUUAUUCCUUUGCCACUGUGUCCUCACCGCACUCUUGGACUCCGCCGAAUGCAGACACCCUCCUGUCUGCAGAAGGAUCUGGAGGGGUAGAACGCUUCCCCUCUACGACGGAUUGACUCCCCAGCACCUCACCAGCAGUUCUUUGAAUGGAGUGGCUUUGGAGGUGGGAGUUGAGGAAGAAAUGUGAGCCUGUCAUUACAGGUUCUGUUUAGAAAACUAGUCAUUCUACUAAAAAGGUAUCACAUAAGUAAGUAGGAGCAAUAAAAACAAAGAAGAUAGUGGGACUCCGAGAAGCUUUCCCCGCCUCUGGCCUGUUAGUCUAUCGUUCGUUGGGCAAGGCUCUUCCAGUGUGUGACCUUUUGCGUGUUAUCACAGCAUGAGUGCAGUUUUGUGUACAGGCAUCCCUAUAUUCAGCAUGUAUCUGCAACAUGCCUUACCUCGUCUGCUGUCACAGAGCAAAGUGGAGCAAGUGGUCGCCGUUGGUCUGCACCUGAGCUGGGAGCCGAGUGGUGACGUGCAUAUGGGCCGACUGCGUCUCCACAGAACCUACUCAGUGAUCUUCCUGUGUACGACUCAGUCCCUGAUGUUGGAGUUGAACUGUAGGACUGUCUGUAAAAUGAAAGUGCAGACUUUAAUGUAGUAAAGAGAAUGACUUGCCAGUUACAACCAAUGAGCAAAGCAGUUAAUUAUUCAAAUAUUUUACCAAGAGUCCAGGUUUAUUUUUUCUCAGGACUACACAUUCUGUGAGACCAGAGGGACCAAGACAUAUCACUACCAGAAAUGUGUUUUCAUCAGCACUGCCAGAGGUUUUCAUAGGGUAGUUUACUCUUGGAAUUUUUAAAUUCAUACUUUUUUUUAUGCAACGUGGGGUAGGUAAGCUUCUGAUCACUGUGCACCCAGAUUAUCCCAAAAUCGAAAGUGGUGUUGGCAGCCGGGUGUGGUGGCUCACACCUGUAAUCCCAGCACUUUGGGAGGCCAAGGUGAGAGGAUUGCUUGAGCCCAGAAUUCGAGACCAGCCUGAGCAACAUAGGGAGACCCUGUCUCUACAAAAAAUAAAAAAAAGGAGCCAGGCAUGGUAGUGCACACCUGUAGUCCCAGCUACUCAGGAGGCUGAGGCGGGAGGAUGGCUUGAGUCCAGGAGGUCAAGGCUGCAGUGAGCCGUCAUUGCGCCAGUGUGCUCCAACCUGGGCCACAGAGUGAGACCCUGUCUGAGGAGGGGAAAAAAGUGUUGUCUAAAUGAGAAAUCACCAUUAUCAGUAAUUUAAGAUUCCAGGCUAUGUUGGUCACAUCUCACUAUUCUUUUUUUUUUGAAACGGAUUCUCGUUCCAUCGCCCAGGCUGGAGUGCAGUGGCACGAUCUGGGCUCGCUGCAAGCUCUGCCUCCUGGGUUCACGCCAUUCUCCUGCCUCAGCCUCCCGAGUAGCUGGGACUACAGGCGCCCGCCACCGUGCCCAGCUAAUUUUUGUAUUUUUAGUAGAGACGGGGUUUCACCGUGUUAGUAGCCAGGAUGGUCUCGAUCUCCUGACCUCGUGAUCCGCCCACCUCGGCCUCCCAAAGUGCUGGGAUUACAGGAGUGAGCCACCGCGCCUGGCCACAUCUCACUAUUCUUAAGGAAGAGAGAGAGCGAGAGAGAGUGUUGUCCUGUCCUGUGGGGAUUGGGGCAUUGUAUUAAGUUGUACUGGGGGAUGUCAAGAUAGAAAUGUUGAGUAAGUUACUACCUGAAUAAAUAUUUGACCAGUUGAUGCUAAUUUGAAUAGUAAAUGUGAUGACAUUAUAUAUUCUCAGGGAUGUUUCCAUACAUUGGCUCUGUGUGUGCGUGUGUGUGUGUGUGUGUGUGUAACAAAAGCAGUAUGAAGUAUGUGAGCAAUAUCCUAAUUUUAUUGACAAGAGCACUGACCUUAAUGACCUUGAGUAAAUUACCCUCUCCGGCUUUGGUUUCCUCAUUUGUCAAUUAAGGGUGAUGGCUAGCGUAUCUUGCAGAUCCAAAUUCCAAUUUUUGUAACAAGCCAAAAGUCCCCCUGGCUGUUAAAGCAAGACCAGAGCCCUCGUAUCCCAGCGGCUGGGUCCCAGGCUUUUGAUUUUCACAGGACAAAUGUAGCCCAGCCAUCUGGAGCCCGUUUUUCUCCAAACCAGGGCUUCCUCCUUCUCUCUUGCAGAUUUCAACUGGGGCUCACCAUUUUCUGCCUCUUCCUCCUCCAGUUUUAAAGAGACACCAUAUCCUUCUCUGCUGGGACCAACUUCCCAUGUACUGCUGCCCUGCACCUGUGAAAACAGCUGCUGUGUUUUCUGUCAUAAAAAUAGCUGCCUUUUGGCAGAGAAGCACACAACGGUACUACGUUUCUGAGCCUUAAUGCAGUGCUCAAUUAUUUAGGUGUGCUUCACCUGAGAUACACAGAGCAUCUUGGAACUCCUACUAAGCAGGGCUUCUACAGGCAUUGCUCAGCUCAGUAAAAGGUUUUCCUUUCUCUGCUUUUGUGAUUACCAGGCAGAAACCUUAAAAUGUAUGAACUUACAAAGAAAUUAAAUUGUGCCAAAUUAGAUUCCCAGCCCCUAGAGAUAACCACUAAUUAAAGUUCCGCUGGAGCGUUUUGCCUGUAUUUUGUAUAUAAACGUGGAUUUUGUAUUUGUAUGUAAAUAAAGGUAGGACCCUGCUGUCCAUAUUAUUUUAAAAUAA